AAAACAGCUUUAUUGAAAUAUAAUUUACAUGAUUUAUUGGAGUAAAUUUACAUAUAAUUUACAUACACAUAAUUCACUCAAUUCAAUAAUGUUUAGUACAUUUACAGAGUUAUGCAACCAUCAUCACAAUCCAGUUGAGAAGAUUUUCAUCAUCCCCAAAAGGAUCCCUCAUGCUUGCUUACGUCCAUCUCUAUGCACACCCCAUAGCUGACCACGCAUCUGCUUUCUGUCUCUUUGUUGUUUUAUUGUUGUAUUUUUUGUCACCCAGGCUGGAGUGCAGUGGCGUGAUCUCUGCUCACUGCAGCCUCAACUUCCUGGGCUCAAGCGAUCCUCCCACCUCAGCCUCCCGAGUAGGUGGGACCACAGGCACACACCAUCAUGCCUGGCUAAUUUUUGUAUUUUUUGUAGAGAUGGGGACUUGUGGUGAUGCCCAGGCUGAUCUUGAACUCCUGAACUCAAUGGAUUCCUCCCGCCUCAGCCUUCCAAAGUGCUGGGAUUAUAGGCAUGAGCCACCUCACCUGGCCUGCUUUCUGUCUCUCCGAAGAUCCAGAGCUGUGUUCAUUCCAGCUGGCCCUGUGACCUCAUGCAAAUUAUUGCCCUUCCAUUACUCCUCUGUAUGAGAGGGAAUAAUCCUACCCUCCUUGUAGGGGGUUGUUUGAAUUUCACUAAUGUGCACAGUGUCUGACGCACCCGAGGAGCUGGGCACGUGGGAGGCUGGUACGCAGGGCACAGGACAUAACACAGAUGCCCAGGUACGGUUGGCACAGGCCUAGCAAACAUUUUAAAGCACUCACUCUGUGCCAGCUUCUUAGAUUAAGCAUCUUACAUGCAUUACCUACUUUAAUCCUCGGUGAAUGUGAGUAUCAGUUUCAUUUUAUAACUGAAGAAACGGGCACUGAGACGGGAAGUCACUUUUACAGGCUCACAUAGAUGAUAGUUGAUAGGGCUGGGAGUCCAUCUGAGAGCCUGUCCUCCCUAAACAUCAUCCUGUCCCCUUCCUGAUGUGAAUCACCAAGCAAGGGACAACACAAUUCAUAGAUCCAGGACAAGGUUUAUGGCACAUACUUCUAAGGGGUGGGACCUGGUAUCAUGGACACGGCAUUCAAGAGAUAGUACAUGGUAUAGAGUCUGUCACAAAACAGACAUCACAUGGUGCAUGAAGCAUGACCCAGGGGUAAGAGGCAUGGGAUGCCGCUAAAGGGAGACACACAGGACAAAGCAAGAGGAACGCAGGGCCUGCUACGUGGCACAGUCACAGGGUAUGUGACACUGGGCAUGACAAACUCUAUGAUGCAGAGACAUGGUACUUAGGAUUUGAGACUUGAGCUAUGGCAACUGGGCAGGCUCUUGGCCACAGUGGGACCCUUUGUCAUCAGGGAUCCUCCAUUAUGUUGGUGCCUGGGGCCCCAGCAAGCAACAGCAGGAACCAAGUUCCUCCUCCUCACAAAGGCAGUCUGUUUUUUUUUUCUUUUUUUUCUUUUUUUCUCCCUCCUCCUCCCUGUCUCUUUGGAUGCCAAAGAGUGGGAGGGGCCCAGCGGAGUGGUGGCCAGAGUAACCCCCCGCCAUCCCAUCAGCUCAGACAAGGGUCAAAGCUUGGGGCCAAGCCCACGGCUCAGGAAGGGUUUGCCAGGCCCCCAGAUCCCCUCUCUCUGAGAUAGCUGUGAGCACCAGUGUUGGCUGGGGUGAAAGCCGGGUAAUUUUCCUCUAAGCUGUCCUCCCUCCGCUCCCCUCCCUGCCUGCUGGUGCUGGCUGUGAGCACGUCUGCAUUCCAGAGCUUAGGAGAGAGAGAACCUGCUGCUGUUAAGGUUGAGGAAGUAGAUUGCUAACAGCUGCUGUAGGAGGGGUUGGAUGUGCGGAAGAGGAGGCCGUGGAUUGCAGGCUAACAUUUCUUGAGCCUCUUGGCACCUGGCACUCACUACCUCAUCUUGUCUCAUUUGCAUAAAGCCCCAGUAGCCCGGUGAGGAGACAGGCCCAGAGAGGCAAAGAACUUGCCUAAGGUCACACAGGGAGGCAGAGCCAAGGCUAGACCUUGGUCUCCCGGAGGCAGGCAGGUGAGGUUGUAUAGAGGUGAUGGCACAGGGGAUGUUGUUGGGGGGUUAGUGGGCAAUGAGACUGCAAGGGCUUGUGGGCCCCAUAUCACAGAGGACCGAACUCAGGAGUCCUGACUUCUUUCUGUCUGCACCGAGGUCUGCAGAAGGGAUGAUGCAAUCUGUAUGAGUGACAGGCCCAGUGCAGAGAGAGUUUAAGGGAGUGAGGGAGCUGAUGUUAUGAUCCCAGGGAAAAGAUGGGGACACCAAACCAGGACAGUGGCUGGAGUGUGGGGGUGAGAAGUGGGUAUAAAGUGGAGAGGAGAUGAGCUUGGUCUCUGCUCUGGUCUCAGCCUUUAUGUACUGUCUUGGUGGGAUGACCGUGGUUGGGUCCUGCCUCCAAGGGUAUCCCAGAGGGUUCUAGAAACUCCCACAUGGACAGGCACUUGAAGGAUAGUGCUGGUGAUUGGGCAGGUGCCUGGAUGGAGGUGAGGCCUAAAGCACACCCGGGGACAGAAGGCAGCACCCACACGGGAGCCCAGCUUCGUGCCAGGGACUGUAUUUUAGGUGCUGGAUCUUGUUUAAAUCUUCCGGCUGGCUAUGAUUAUCCUCUAAGCUGGGGAAGGAAGAAAAGCAUUCCAGUACUAUACCUCUGUUUGGGUUAAAGGAGGGGAAAGUAUUUUAAAUAAAACCUAUUAGAGUUAAAAGGAUGAGUAGCAAUAAAAAUAUCUUUGAAUCUCUGAUGGUUCUAUUGUAGUCAAAAGUUUUAGAUAAAUUGUGAAGAAUCUCUAAUCAUGCUAUGUGGAGUUUUUCUCUUUUAAAAAAUACAAGUUAUUGUAUAUACUUAAGGUAUAUAACGCGAUGUUAUGAAUACAUUUAGAUAGUAAAAAGGUUACUAUAGUGCAGCAAAUGAACAUAUUCAUCAUCUCAGCUGGCACAAAAGUAAUUGCAAUUUUUGCCAUUACUUUCAAUGACGAAAACUGCAAUACUUUUGCACUGCACUAAUAAAAUCUGCUCAUUUAGCAUGAAUCCCAAAAUACAGUACAACUUAUUCCCUAUAGUCCUCAUGUUGCACAUUAGUGCUCUUUUUUAUUUUUAAAUUUUUAUUUUUGUUAUUUUUAAUAUAGAGAGAGACAGGGUCUCACGACAUUGUCCAGGUUGGUCUUGAACUCUGGGGCUCAAGUGAUCCUCCCUCCUCAGCCUCCCAAAGUGCUGGGAUUACAGGCACAAGCUCUCUACACUUGUUCAUUCCACGUAUCUGCUACCUUGCACCCUCCAUAUCCUCAUUCGUGGAUUCAACCAACCACAGAUCAGAAAUAUUAAAAAAAAAUAAAAAUUAAAAAAAGUAAAAAUAAUACAAAUUUUAAAAACAGUGCAGUGUAACAACUAUUUACAUAGUUUAUUGUUACAUAGAAAUUUACAUUUACAUUUUUAUGUAACAACUACAGUAUAACAACUAUGUAAAUAGCAUUUACAUUGUAUUAGGUUUUAUAAGUAAUCUAGAGAGAUUUAAAGUUUAAUACAUGGGAGAAUAUAUGUAGGUUGUAUGCAAAUACUGUACUAUGCCAUUUUAUAUAUUGGUGUACAGCAUCUGCAGAUUUUGGUAUCUGAGGGAGGUCCUGGAACCAACUGAUCCCGCGUGGAUAGGGAGGGACAACUAUUCUCUGAUAUGUCUCCCCACUGGACUUUUUUUUUUUUUUUUUUUUGAGUUGGAGUCUUGCUCUGUCACCCAGGCUGGAGUGCAGUGGCGCGAUCUCGGCUCACCGCAACCUCCAUCUCGUGGGUUCAAGCCAUUCUCCUGUCUCAGCCUCCUGAGUAGCUGGGACCACAGAUGCCCACCACCAUGCCCGGCUAAUUUUUUGUAUUUUUAGUAGAGAUGGGGUUUCACCAUGUUAGCCAGGCUGGUCUCGAACUCCUGGCCUCAAGUGAUCCACCUGCCUCCGUCUCCCAAAGUGCUGGAAUUACAGGUGUGAGCCACUGCACCUGGCCCCCAUUGGACUUUUUCUCUAACUGAUUUGUACUUGUAUCAAGUUCUGGUGAGUCCGUGAGAUAAUAUGGCCAUUCUAUCCCUGUGGACACUGAAGCUCAGAGAGGUUGUGUCCCUUGCUCAGCAUCACUCAGUUGUAAGUGCUAGGACUGGGAUCCAGAGCCCUCACUUUUUUGUUUUUGGUUUUUUGCUUUUUUGAGUCAGGGUUUCACUCUGUCACCCAGGCUGGAGUGCAGUGGCACAAUCAUAACUUACUGUAGCCUCGACUUCCCAGGCUCAAGUGAUCCUCCCACCUCAGCCUCCCCAGUAGCUAGAACUACUGGUGCAUGUCAUCACGCCUGGCUAAUUUUUUAAUUUUGUGUAGAGACAGGGUCUCACUCUGUUUCCCAGGCUGUUCUCAAACUACUGGGUUUAAGCUAUCCUCCUGCCUUGGGCUCCCAAAGUGCUGGGAUUACAGGCAUGAACCACCAUGCCCAGCCAAGAGCCCUUGUUCUUUUGGGUGAGGCAGAACAGGCAAAGUCAGAGAGGAGGGGAGGGGGUGUCAUUAGGAGUCUCAUGGAGGGGAUUGGGUAGCAAGGCUGGCUCUGUAGGUGUUGGCUUGAGGCCCUCUCCUGAGAUGCAUCCCCAUCCCUGGUACCAGCCUUGUUUGGAACCCUCCCUGUCUCCCUUGCUUUGUAUGCAAAGACACAGAGGUAGAGGGCUAGGUAUGAGGUAGGUAUAGGGCAGGUAUAGGGGCCAGUGAGCUGUAUGUGUGUAUAGGGUCUGGACACAUGCUGUAGGUCAUCUUUGGAUGUUAUGCUUACUGAGCACCUGCUGUGUGCCAAACACAGUGCCAGGGCUCCUUCAGUCCUACCAGACACCCCACCAGGUUGGCAUCUUCACCUCAUUUUACAGAGGAGGAAAUUGAAGUGCCGCAGAAGGUGCCACUGGCUCAAGUUCCCUGGUGGUAGGGAUUUGGGCUCUGUCCAGAUUCAUCCCUGUACAUUGCCUCAUAUUCCUUAGGUUGGAAGGUCACUUGUCCUCACCCUGUUGGUCAUUUUUGGUAUCUCCAGCCCACAGAGACUCCGCAGGCACUCCUGGAUCCCAUUGUCUUUUCCCUCUUCCCCGCACCUGCCCCCUUUUGUCUUUCUCAGGGAGUUCUCCCUGCAGAGUGCCUUUGCGGGGCAUGGUCCACGGAUCCCUCACAUUUAUGGUCUCAUUUAAUCGUCUCAACUAGCCUUCAAGAAAGGCACUUUGACCCCGAUUUUCCACAUCCAGACAAUGGGCUCACACUUCCUGCCAGAGCCCAGCAAGGAGGAAAUCUUGGCCAUAGUUGGUAUGGGAGGCUUGGGGACACAGAAGGGCUUUGUUUGAAGCCAGCAGCAGGAGGGAUGUGGCACCAUCAUCUGAUGUGCUGCAUCAUUCAUUGUCCCCAUCGGGAAGGUGGUUGGCCUGGGGAAGCUUCCAGCAUUCCUGGUAGAUCCCAGUGAAGGAUGAAUCUGAUCCCUAGGCAGGCAGGAGGGGACCCUGGCCAGAUGCACAAACUUGUUUGCUUUUUGCUGUGUGUCUUUUAGCAUCCUUGAGUCCCAGGGCCUGAAGGGUUCUUGGACAUGGGCCGAUUUUCCUGUCACCUAUGUCCCCUCAACCUCAUCACCACUGGGCAGCUCAUUAUCUCUCUGGAAAAGGGGAAGGAAACCAGCAUUUGUCUUUCCAUUUUUUUUUUUUUAAACUGUGGAAACAUACACACAUCAUAAAAUUUGCCAUUUAAUAGGCCGGGCGCGGUGGUUCACACCUGUAAUCCUAGCACUCUGGGAGGCCGAGGAGGGCAGAUCACUUGAGGUUAGGAGUUCGAGACCAGCCUGGCCAACGUGGUAAAACCCCGUCUCUACUAAAAAUACAAAAAUUAGCCAGAAAUCACUUGAACCUGGGAGGCGGAGGUGGCAGUGAGCCGAGAUCACGCCGCUGCACUCCAGCCUGGGUGACAGAGCGAGACCCCAUCUCAAAAAAAAAAAAAAAAAAGAAAGGCAUUUUUAACCCUAUCUUACAUGUAAGGAAAUUGAGGCUCAGAGAGAUAGAAACUUAUCCAAGUCUCUCUUUUAACAAUAAAAGCAGCCUCCUUUAUAUGUGCUUAUUCUGUACCAAGCACUGUGCUAAGCCCCAAAUGUUCUUUACCUUAUUAAAUUCACACAACUACCCUAGGAAAAAAGUAUUAUAAUCCCCGUUUUAUAGAUGAGGAAACGGAGGCUCAGAGAGCCAAAACAACUUGCUCAAAGCCACACUGCUAAUAAGUGAUAGACCGGGGACUUAAAUGCAGGCAUUUCUGGUGGGAGCUCUUUCCACGAUCACAUAACAGAAGGUUGCUCUCUGUUUUUCUCCCUCUUGGAAAGUCCUUCCUCUGCAGAGCAGGAAGCUGCCUCCUGUGGCUUCUCCUGCUCAUUCUGGCUUGGGUUGGGGCAUUGUAGACCCUGCCUUCCCCUGCAGCUCUGCAGAGCCUGUGACUCUCCAAAGUCUUCUGCUGGUUCCACGGUCCCAGCAUCUGCAGCCAGGCCUCCCUGUCUUGUUGUGGAUUUGCGUUUGUGCCUGGGCUUCCCAGGGGUGGGUGGUGGGGUGCUGAAGGGGCUAGGACAGUUAUUUGCAGCCCUGGCUACUGACCCACCACACCUCUCAGGGCCAUUUCCUCCCCGAGAGAAGGGGAGACAGACUGCUGAAGUGGGUCCUAGCAAGAAGGGCCCAGAGCUCAUACCCAUGGCCAAAUCUGGCUGCUUCCAGGACAUGGGGUCAGGAAGUAGCAGGGCCAGGCCCCUCCAGAUGUCCAGCCCUGGGUCCCAGCACUAGGUGGGGCUGGCUCCGGAAGCUGGGAAAGGACCAUGGCUUUGGUCCCUGAGACAGUUGGUCUCCUGGAGUUGGCUUCAGCCAAGCCCCGCUGGCCAUCUCCCCAACAGCUGGCCACUCCCAGGAUGGACUUGGCCAAAGCAGAAGGCCAGCCAGCCCCGAUGGGGAGCACUGCUGUGUCAUGGAGACCCAGGCCUCAGUUCUGGCCUGGUUGUUGAGAGACCUGAGUUCUAGAUCUACUCUGCCAGGCACUUGUUUGACUUUGUGACCCUGAAAAGUCACCCUCUUGUUCUUGGUGUGAUCAUCUACAAAAGAGAAGACAGACUAAUGAACACUGCUGCUAAUAAGUCCUGCUCUGAACAACAUACUCCAACAGUCUCACUUCUGUUCCCCCAAAAGUCCUGCAACUGGGCAUCACUGUCCCUGUUUACAGAUGAGUGACCUGAGGCUCAGAGAGGGAAGGUAACUUGCUCUGCCUUACACAGCCCAGACCUGAACUCUAGCGUCUCACCGUGAAAUCUGUAACGUUUCUCCCGCACCAUCACAUACCGAAGGCAGGCGUCUGUGCAGAAAACAGGCUGCUCAGAAAGAAGAGUGCUUACUUUUGGCGAGCUCCUGUGCGUCACAUCCUGGGCUUCCUCACUGCUCCAUGCUCUAGGUACCAUUCUCCCCCUUUUAGAGAUGAGGAAACUGAGGUCUGGAUUGCAGAAGCUGAGUCCAGAUUCGCAAACCUGUCCACAGGGCUUGCCGGAACUUUUCCAGGCCCUGUUCAGUUCCACUGGGUUUCAUAACUGGCUUCUCUGUUUACUGACCAUUGUCCCAAUUAGCAAAAUCCCUGGUCAGAAGGGCGGGUGCUCCUAGGAGGACCCAGAGAACAGCAGUGAGCCAAAAAGUAAAUAGACUCCAAGAGAGGGCUUUCCAUGAGUGGCUGGCUGCCUGGAAAAUCAAGAACAACAGUGUUUGGAGUGAAGAGAAAAGAACAGGGUGGUGUCUUCCAGGCCCAGCCAAGGCCUUUUUGUACACUGUGGCUGGGGAUGGAAGGGGCGGGGGAGGCCACCUCCUCUGGUCUCUGGUAGGGGGUCCCGCAGACAUACAGAGACCAAGGUUACAGAGGAAAGGAGGGCCCAGAGCUGGUUGUGUUGUGGAGGUCCUGGGUCAACUACAGGGGAGGGAGGGGUCCCCCAGGGGGACAUGGGCUGUACAGCCCCCAUCCUGUGGCAGACACAGAGAAUCUGCCUACUGUGUGCCUGGAGCUGGGCAGGAUCCAGGAAUAGCCGAGAUCAGAGGUCAAGGAGAUCUCCGAGGUGCACAGAAGCAGAGACCAGGACAUGCUCAUGUACUGAGUUGGUAGCAGAAGGGCUGCCUCCAAAUCAAAGAAACCAUGCCAGACCUGAGUGCCAUGUGGCUCAGAGGGCAGGUGCCACAGCCAGUCCUGCACUAAAUGGCCACAGCCUGGGGAUCUUCCAGGCCUUUGGCCUGGGCAGUCACAUCAGGUGUGUGAAAGGCUAGAGGGCUUUCCCGGUGUCACCUCCUGCCCUGGCCUGGGAAGUGUCGUGGGGACAGCUGCUCCGGAGACUCCUGGCUGCCAGGCUUGACUUGGGCUUGAUUGAUUUAGCCUGUUACCUGGAAAGGGCACUGCUGCUCCCUGCCCAGGUCAGGUGGUGCUAGGAGCUCCUGCUUGGUCUCCGCAGACAGAGCCUGGGCUCUGAAGCCAGUCAGACUUGUGUUUGAAUCUUGGCAACACCUCUUUCCAGUUGAGUGACUUGAACCUCCCUGAGUCUCAGUUUCCCAGGCUGGGCCCAGAGGUGAGGUGGCAUGCUGCUAUCAGUGACUGCAGUGCCUCCUUCCUCAAGUCAGGGGCUGUGGACUGUCUGAUCCAGAACGGCCUGCAGAGGUGACCUGGCCGAAUGUACCCAUUUUACAGAUGGAACCCUGAAGCUCAGAGACUUGUAGGUCCUGGAUUUGGUUGUACAACCAGUAUCUGGUACUGCUUGGGCUAGGAAAGAGGCUUCGAGUCAGAGCAUCAGGCCCUACCCUGUAUUUUGCAUAUGAAGACACUGAAACCCAGAAAGGUACAGUGACUUGCCCAAGGUCACCAGGAAGUCAGUGUCAGAGCCAGCCCUAGCACUCGGGCCUCUUCCUUUCCACCUAGGGGUCCUUCUCUUGUACCUGAAUUCCCCCAUUCCCUUGAACUCAUACAUCUUCUUCCAGGCUGGAAGCAGAGUAAGACAAUGUUGCCCGCAUCAUGGUCUCCACUCAUCAGUGCCCUGUAGCAAGGGCUCCAGGGUCUGUAGUGAGGGCUCCCAGAGGGCAAGGGUGGGGUCUGUUCACCAGCUCUCCUGUGCCAAGGGCCUGGGCUCCAGAGCUAUAUGGCAGGCAAAGCUGCAGGCCCUUUGUGAUCAUUAACGUGGUCCCUGGGUUGAUGGCCAGUGGCCUCUGGGGCCAAGGUCAAGCCACAGCAGCCCCUCUAUUAAUCACCAACUAUGCAGGUCAGAGUCACACUGCUCUGGAAGGGGCCCCUCAGCUGGGCAGUUGCUGGCCCAGGUUCAGUCUGGGGGCUGGGCAGCUAAGAAAAUUUCUUCCUACUUGUUUGAAUUUUCCAAAUUGUCUAAUGAGCAGGCAUCACUAUAAGCAUAUUUUAAAAGGGAUUGUUUCUGGAUUUGUGUUUUAUAAAAGAACAAAACUAUAUUGGAUAUACACUUGUAAAGUUUCAAAUGCUACGGCAAUGCUUUUACAAUUUUUUCGGCUAGUAUAUUAAGGUAUAAUUUACAUAUCAUAGUGAUUCACACACUAAGUAUACCUAUAGUUCUAUGAAUUUUAGUAGAUUUAAUUGGUUAUAUAAUCUUCACCAUAAUCUAGUAUUAGAAUAUUUUUAUCACCCCGAAAAGUUCCCUCAUGCCAACUGCAGUGAUCUAGGCACUUCCUCCAGCCUCAGGCAGCCACGGCAAUGUUUGAGGAUGAAAUUCUCCUCCUUCUUCCCUUUCCAGCAAACGGCCUUAACAGUUUGGUGCUUACCCUCUGAUUUUUUAAGGGUAUAUGCAAAAACAGGCACCAUUGUAAAAAGGAGAAGAGGAGAUAUACUAUAGCCAUUGUUGUGCAAUUGCUUUCUGCACUUGGAGAUCUCCCUGUGUUUAUUGAGUGCCUACUAUAUGCCAGGCACAAUCAGACGUAGCUCAUUCUUUUUUCACAGCUGCAUAGUGUCUAUUGUAAUGGUGGCUCCAUCAUUUAUUUAACCAGGACUUUUGGGUCCUUUCCAGUUUUCUUCAAACAAUGCUUCAGUGAACAUCCUUGCACAUAUAUUUUUGUGUUUGUUGUUCUUGCAGAUACAGCGCUAGGAAAAGGGGAGUAAUUCAGGUCUAGAAUGGAAAAACUGUUUUGUUGCUUUCCCAACAGCAUGGUGGUGGAACACCCCGAGUUCCUCAAGGCAGGGAAGGAGCCUGGCCUGCAGAUCUGGCGUGUGGAGAAGUUCGAUCUGGUGCCCGUGCCCACCAACCUUUAUGGAGACUUCUUCACGGGCGACGCCUACGUCAUCCUGAAGACAGUGCAGCUGAGGAACGGAAAUCUGCAGUAUGACCUCCACUACUGGCUGGGCAAUGAGUGCAGCCAGGAUGAGAGCGGGGCGGCCGCCAUCUUUACCGUGCAGCUGGAUGACUACCUGAACGGCCGGGCCGUGCAGCACCGUGAGGUCCAGGGCUUCGAGUCGGCCACCUUCCUAGGCUACUUCAAGUCUGGCCUGAAGUACAAGAAAGGAGGUGUGGCAUCAGGAUUCAAGCACGUGGUACCCAACGAGGUGGUGGUGCAGAGACUCUUCCAGGUCAAAGGGCGGCGUGUGGUCCGUGCCACCGAGGUACCUGUGUCCUGGGAGAGCUUCAACAAUGGCGACUGCUUCAUCCUGGACCUGGGCAACAACAUCCACCAGUGGUGUGGUUCCAACAGCAAUCGGUAUGAAAGACUGAAGGCCACACAGGUGUCCAAGGGCAUCCGGGACAACGAGCGGAGUGGCCGGGCCCGAGUGCACGUGUCUGAGGAGGGCACUGAGCCCGAGGCGAUGCUCCAGGUGCUGGGCCCCAAGCCGGCUCUGCCUGCAGGUACCGAGGACACCGCCAAGGAGGAUGCGGCCAACCGCAAGCUGGCCAAGCUCUACAAGGUCUCCAAUGGUGCAGGGACCAUGUCCGUCUCCCUCGUGGCUGAUGAGAACCCCUUCGCCCAGGGGGCCCUGAAGUCAGAGGACUGCUUCAUCCUGGACCACGGCAAAGAUGGGAAAAUCUUUGUCUGGAAAGGCAAGCAGGCAAACACGGAGGAGAGGAAGGCUGCCCUCAAAACAGCCUCUGACUUCAUCACCAAGAUGGACUACCCCAAGCAGACUCAGGUCUCGGUCCUUCCUGAGGGCGGUGAGACCCCACUGUUCAAGCAGUUCUUCAAGAACUGGCGGGACCCAGACCAGACAGAUGGCCUGGGCUUGUCCUACCUUUCCAGCCAUAUCGCCAACGUGGAGCGGGUGCCCUUCGACGCCGCCACCCUGCACACCUCCACUGCCAUGGCCGCCCAGCACGGCAUGGAUGACGAUGGCACAGGCCAGAAACAGAUCUGGAGAAUCGAAGGUUCCAACAAGGUGCCCGUGGACCCUGCCACAUAUGGACAGUUCUAUGGAGGCGACAGCUACAUCAUUCUGUACAACUACCGCCAUGGUGGCCGCCAGGGGCAGAUAAUCUAUAACUGGCAGGGUGCCCAGUCUACCCAGGAUGAGGUCGCUGCAUCUGCCAUCCUGACUGCUCAGCUGGAUGAGGAGCUGGGAGGUACCCCUGUCCAGAGCCGUGUGGUCCAAGGCAAGGAGCCCGCCCACCUCAUGAGCCUGUUUGGUGGGAAGCCCAUGAUCAUCUACAAGGGCGGCACCUCCCGCGAGGGCGGGCAGACAGCCCCUGCCAGCACCCGCCUCUUCCAGGUCCGCGCCAACAGCGCUGGAGCCACCCGGGCUGUUGAGGUAUUGCCUAAGGCUGGUGCACUGAACUCCAACGAUGCCUUUGUUCUGAAAACCCCCUCAGCCGCCUACCUGUGGGUGGGUACAGGAGCCAGCGAGGCAGAGAAGACGGGGGCCCAGGAGCUGCUCAGGGUGCUGCGGGCCCAACCUGUGCAGGUGGCAGAAGGCAGCGAGCCAGAUGGCUUCUGGGAGGCCCUGGGCGGGAAGGCUGCCUACCGCACAUCCCCACGGCUGAAGGACAAGAAGAUGGAUGCCCAUCCUCCUCGCCUCUUUGCCUGCUCCAACAAGAUUGGACGUUUUGUGAUCGAAGAGGUUCCUGGUGAGCUCAUGCAGGAAGACCUGGCAACGGAUGACGUCAUGCUUCUGGACACCUGGGACCAGGUCUUUGUCUGGGUUGGAAAGGAUUCUCAAGAAGAAGAAAAGACAGAAGCCUUGACUUCUGCUAAGCGGUACAUCGAGACGGACCCAGCCAAUCGGGAUCGGCGGACGCCCAUCACCGUGGUGAAGCAAGGCUUUGAGCCUCCCUCCUUUGUGGGCUGGUUCCUUGGCUGGGAUGAUGAUUACUGGUCUGUGGACCCCUUGGACAGGGCCAUGGCUGAGCUGGCUGCCUGAGGAGGGGCAGGGCCCACCCAUGUCACCGGUCAGUGCCUUUUGGAACUGUCCUUCCCUCAAAGAGGCCUUAGAGCGAGCAGAGCAGCUCUGCUAUGAGUGUGUGUGUGUGUGUGUGUUGUUUCUUUUUUUUUUUUUUACAGUAUCCAAAAAUAGCCCUGCAAAAAUUCAGAGUCCUUGCAAAAUUGUCUAAAAUGUCAGUGUUUGGGAAAUUAAAUCCAAUAAAAACAUUUUGAAGUGUG